AGUGGAAGCAUGGGCGGCGAGCCGGGCCGUGCUCUCGGGGCGCGGGGUCCCCAUUUUGGGCGAGGGCGGCCGCUCCCGCGCUCGGGGUGGGCGCGCCCCAUCCCCGUCCCCCGUUUCCCGUCCCCGUCUCCCGGCCGCAUCUCCGUCCCCCCGCAGCCGCGAAACGCGGGGAGGUUCCAGGGCCCGCGGCCGCGGGUUCGCGAGCACCGCGCUCCAGAUCGAGAGCGGCGCGCGCCCUUCCGUGGAGGACAGAGGGGCGCGGAGGGGGCGCCUGUGUCCCACCCGCUCGCGGGCGCUUUACGGGGCGUCCUCUGCGCCAUUCACUUGUCAGCUUGUCGGGAAGUUGAAAUCGCGUUUGGGAGGGGCGUCCUCUCCCCCCACCGCUGCAGGAGCACCCCCUUCCUUCCUCGGAAGCGUCCUCUCACCACACCGCUUCAAGAGCCCCCCCUUCCUUCCACAGGGGCGUCCUUUCCCCCUCCGAGGCAGGAGCGCCCCUUUUCCCCCCACAGGAGCGCCCUCCCCACCCCAGGAGCGCCCUGCGCCCAGCAGACGGGCAGGUGGGCGGGCGUCCACUACCUGUGUGCGCGGUGCGGGCGGUGACUGCCAAGUUGGAGAUGCCCUUGGAGAACUGCUUCGAAUUCAUGUAUCUACUGGGCUUUUGUGACUUUCAAAGCCUAUAGCAAAUAAGCACCCCUGCAAUUACGUCUCCUCAAUGACCAAGUCAGGGUGAGGUGAGGGCUUCCUGAGUUCAGAUCCCAGCAAGCUCCCGAUCCUGCGCAACGAAGAAAACUCAACAAAACAGGCUUUGGCUGUUUAUUUUAUUUUUUUUUUAAUUGUGCCUUCAUGAAAUAAUUUACAGCAAUAAUUUAUCUUAUAAUAUUGGUUAUUGUUUUUAAGUCCCGGAUGUUUACUUUUGGAUGUCCUCUAUAAUUCAUAGAAGUAUCUUAAAAGUAAUAAAAUCUUAAUCUAAGAGAAAAUAAGUGUAAUUUUUGAAAGAGUGAUAUAUAUUUUAAUAUGUUUUUGUAACAUGUGACUUGAAGAUUGUGUUGGCUAAUUUUAUGUGCCAAGAGAGCCCUGACUAGUACAAAGAUUAUAGCGUUUUUAUUUUUAGCAUGUAUACAGUUAGGAUUAUUGAUCAGUAGCCUGAAUUUGGGAAGAAUAAUCAUUGUGGCAAAUAUCACCCAGUGUGCCUCAAAAAGGUGUGUUUAAAGUUGAUCUUCCAUUUUUAAAUCAUACCUUAAAAAAAAAUACCUCAAGAAAUGCCAUUUUAAGUCUGUGCACCUAUGUGUGCAUGUGUGCGUGUUUGUUUAUAUAAUAGAUUGUGUGAUUGUGUGUGUAUAGGUAUGUGUGUAUGAUUGUGUGUGUUGGGGGCGCCACCUUUAUGAACAUUAUGCUUCGGCGUUCUUUUUAGAUCUUGUUACCUUUUCUUACGUUCACAAAUGUUGCCUAGCAAUAUGUCUAGUCAGGAAAGAUGAAGGGAUUCUUAUCUUGGUGCUUGAAGAAAAUGUGGUGUAGUUUUAUUGGCUUUGUGAUCACUUACAUCCCACUUUUAUGAGGAUGUAAAUGGGCCACCUCUAUGUUCCUGUAUGUUGCCAGCCAUCAGUAGACAAUGCUAAAGGAACCACCACUUUUAAACAUCAUGUGAUGGUUUCUUCUGAGAAAGUAUAUUUUGCAAUCUUUUUCUUUUUCAUGUUGACUUUUAUUAUGCAGUUGCAUUUUCAUAUCCGUAUUGAACAUUUACUUGCUGUGCCUGUCACACGCUAGCAGGUGUCAUCUUUUCCUGUUUGCUUGUUUCUUGGGGCCAUCCUAGUGUUAAAGGCCAGUGUUUUUAAGGUGUCAGCAGCUCUGGAUUGGCAGUUAGCACUUUCCCCAUGUACUGCCUCAGUUACCAGACUGGGGACAAAAGAGAGAAGGUUAAAGAAUUAUCACCUAUGUCCGUGGUAUUCUGUCAUAGAGAGUAUAAAUUUCCUACAGCAAACUGGAAAUUAAUUGCAAUUCUGCAGUUAGAACCUCCAAAUACAAAUGUGGAUGAUACAAUUUCAAUUCUCAUUGAGAGUCAGCCCAUGAAACAAACCAACAGUAAGAAACUCUGUAAUUAGAAGUAUCCCAGUCCUCUUCCUCAACCGAGGAACUUGUUUUCUUUCCCCCUUUCUAUUGCCAGAUAAGCUAUUUAUUUAUUUAAAGCUUGUUCUACACCUUGUGAUUUUCCAACUGUUCUUCCAUACUUUUUCAACAAAAGUCAGCUAAUAACAUCUGCCAACAUGCUCUGCACGCAGGACUGGCUGGGGCUGGCAUGGCCUCUUGCCAGCAAACAGCCUGGUUGAAAUUUUUUCUCAUGGUCCAAGAUCUUUCCUUGGAAGCUUUCUUUCCUUUCACAGCUAAUAAAAUGGCCAUAUCUUUCAGCAGGGAGUUUUUUCUGUUUGUUUGUUUUUUCUAUUUUUAACAGAAUCAUAUACAAUAAUGAUUAUUUUAUUAGAAGUCUUCUGAAAUAAUUACUUUUCAAGAAAGAAUCAAUUAUAUAAAAGUGUAGAGAUUUAAAAAUAUGUUACAGGUUCACAAUACAAAUACUAGUAGCACUACCAAUAAUGAACAUCACUAAUUAUUUUCUUUGUUUCAUAUAGGAAAGGCAAGUAUGGGAGGAGAAAGGUGAAUAGCAUUUUAUUGCUUGUGAAAUUUUCUUUCUUUUUUUAGUUCUUUGCCCUGUAGGUGUUUGACAGUAUUUUGUAUUUAGGUGAGCUCAAUCUAAAAACUAAGCAGAUUAAGUGGAAUGCUAUAUAACUAGUUAGAAUAGCUUUAAUUUAAAAGGUAUUUUAAGAGGGAAAGAUUUUUAACUUCACAGGUUUCUGUCAAAGGAUAUAUUUAAUCUUUAAAAUGAGUGGCACCAUUUCAUUAUAUUUCAUUUUAUUAGAUAAUGUUGUUCAGUAGCUCAUUUGAGAAAUUCCAUUCCUCUGAUGAACGAACUGUGGACAGACUUUUCCUCAUCUAGGGUUUAUAAGGAAACUUCUUGCACUUUACCAGCAAAUUUAUUUGCUAAUGUUUCAACUGAAAUUUCACAAGAGUUUUGUAACAUGCUAACUCUGUGUAUGGGCAACAGAAUGACUUACAUGAGAGAAUAUAACUGCUGUUUGGAUCAUUUGCUAUGUAUGGCAUUGCAAACAUUUAAAGUAUCAGGAUUUGUUAAUGGAAUUGAUCAGCCCCUUGGAAAUUAUAAAGGCUUUCUACUUGUGUGUUUAUUAUUCUUGUUAAAAAUAUGGAUCAGUCUCUUUCCUAAAUGUUCAUUUUAUGAGGGAGGAUUUUCUAAAAUAAAUGAUUAUUUAAUGUGCAUAUAUGAUAGAACAAACUACUAUAACUUUUUUAAAGUCUUAUCAAUUGAAUUAAUACUGUUUAGAAAAAUAUGUUGUAGUUACAAAUGCAGCUAAUCCAGUAUUCUCAACAUUUUUUCAUUAUAAAUAUAAUUAUGUUGAAGAAAUACAUAAAUGCCCAAUUAAAAAGUGACUGCGGUUAGGAGUUGAAAAUAUUUAUUAAUAUGCCUCUGGAUUUUGUUCUGUUUGAAUUUUGAGAAUGUGUUUCUAGAUUUAAGAAGCAACACAAGCUUUUUUUCCCAGAAGGCUUCCUAUUAUUGAAAUGGAAAUUAUACAUUAAUGACUGUAUAACACUAGUAGAUAUUUUUAAAAUGCAAGAGCAUCUUCUUAGAUCAUUACUUUUCCUUGGAAUGCUUGGCCCCUGUAAUAUAAUACACCGGUAUUUUGCAUGAUGAAA